ACGCGCUGCGCUCCCUGCGCCGCCGUCCGCACCGCGCUCGGAAUGGGGCGUCACGCCGUGGCAUUUUGUGCCUUCUGCAAACUGGUCGUGUUCGAAUUGCGUUUUUUUGGUGCCUACAUGUCGUGCGUGCUGGUUUUCUGCGGCCCGGCGCUCCGCUUCUUCCUCGCGCAGGCUGAGAGGACGGGUGGGGGCACGUCGCCCUCGCGCGGGAGAAGGGAGGCCGGGCGUCCGGGUUGGCCUGAGUUGGCUGGGGUGCUUCGCCGACCACCAGGCUGCCCGGCGCUUGGCCCCUUGCAGUGCGAGCCCCAGGCCUUCCUGACGGAAAGCUUCGCUUCUGGCUCCUAGUCGCCCUCAGUUACCAGACCUCCCCAGCGCCCCACUCCUCUCUGCCAGCCGAGUGUGAAGACCCUCACUGUGCCCCCCACCCCGGAAUCCCUCGUCUGAGGAUUAAGCACAUAACUUCCCAUUUUCAUCGGGAUCCAGACAAUCCCAUUCUGUCCAGGUGGAAAGAUUCUCUGAAUUUAAGUCUUGGGAAUGCAGCAGCGAAAUUUAACCUUUAGUCCCGAAGUAGUUUUUUUGCCUUCUCUCGCACAUACAACUUUUAGAGUCUUCUGACAACUGUGCUGCUUUAGGUUAUCUUGAGAUUCUUAAGUUAAUGCCUUGAGGCCGUGUGAUGGGAGUUUCAAAGAGAAGGCUUUUACAGCUUUUCUUCCACCUGUAUCGCAGUUUGAAAUGGAAAACGUGAGUUGAUGAUGAUUUUCCAUACGAGAUGGAUUUCAGUUUGCAGCCCCGGCUGCCGUGGCUCACUUGGUUAUUUGGUGCCUACCCCUGAAGUUGAUUUUAAAGCUUAAAAUAGUGGUUAGGUAAAGGAGCUGCUGAAAAAGAAGUUCAGUACAAUUCAAUAGAGCCAUUCUAUUGGCUUCUAUUAACGUGUUUAACCUUAAGCUUUAACCAUGACAGGAGUUUCAUGUAGGAACCCACAUACCAAGUGAAAUAUUGAAUUUUAAUUAGUGCGUUCCAGGUCUGACUUGGAUUAGAUUCUUCUCGGCUCCCACUCCCUUUUGGUAUACAUUUUCCUUAGGGUCCUGUACUGUAUUUAAUGAAACAGUUUUAGUAUUGAGGAUUAGAGGAGUACCUCUUGAAUCACGAAACUUUCUUUGACAUGCUUGAAAACAAUGAAUAGGUAAAAUCUGAAGCAUGAUACUUGCAAUAAGGUAGGAAAUAGUAAAUUUUUUAACAUCACCAGUUUGCAAAGGUUAAGAUGGCUUCUUUAGUCUUGAUUUGAAAAUUGUGUUGGCAUUUUAAUCUUAUGCAUCACAGAAAUACAGAAUUUUCGAUGUUUAAGGAACAUUAACAGUAUAAUCCAAUCCCAUUAUUUUAUAGAGAAAUUAAGAAUCGAAGACAGUUUCUUGAUGAGAUUUAGCAGGAGCUGAAUAGAACUAGUAGUCUUCAUUAACUAAACACUUAACUAGGUAAUUCAGACCUCUUGUACUAAAGUUUGUUUGAUUAUGGUACUAAAGUUUGUUUGAUUAUGGUAUCUUAAAAAGCCAAGUAAUUAAAUGAAAUUUUUUUCCUUAAUUUAUGAUUUGGACCCAUUAGAUUAAAAUGCCAUGAAUUGUACAUAGUUAGGAAGUAUUUACAUUCUGUGAGUUUAAACAUUACUUUCCAGUGUUUUUGAAUUAGCAAUUAUCUUGCGCUUCAAGAAUCGAUUCAUAUUUUUGAUUCGGAUAGCCUACGUCACUUCCAGCAGAUUGGUAUUUUAAGAGUCUUAGAGUUAUGGUGUAUAUAAACCGUGGUUUAGUCAUGUGUCAUUUAAUGACAGGUAUGUUCUGAGAAAUGUGUACUUGUGGGAGCAUCAUAGAAUGUACUCACACAAACCUACAUGGUAUAGCCUACUUCACACCUAGGCUAUAUGGUAUAUAGCUUAUUAGUCCUGGGCUACAUCCCUGUUCAGCAUGUUACCGUACUGAAUACUGUGCCUAAACACACCUAAACUUAGAAAGGGUACAGUAAAAAUACGGUAUUAUAAUCUUAUGGGACCACAGUUGUAUAUUCGAUGUUUUGUUGACUGAAAUGUCAUGUGAUGCAUGACUAUCACUUAGGAAGGGAAAUCCUAUCACAUGUAAUAAUCUAAUUCCAGCACGCCCAAUCUCGCAUUUCAAAGUGGACCUCAAGUGCAUGAGUCCUGAAGUUCUUGCUGUGGUGCGAUGAAUUUUUUACAUCCCAGAGUACAGUGUUUAGUGUAGACAUUUAGUAAAUACUUGUUGGCCUGUGCGCACUUUCCUGGUAGGCGCUUCGUGAAAGUUCGGCUAUGUCCUACUCAUCUGUGUAUACCUGUUAUCAUGUGUAGUGGGUACUCUUUAAAUGCUUAUGAUCUUGUUGGGCUUAAUCUAAUUUUUGAAGGUAGCAGAGUGCCUGGAAGUCCUGAAUCAUGAUAUAGUAAACUUGAACUAACUCAGUUCCUUUUUUGUGUUGAACCAGGUACGCUGUUAGGUUGAAUUCCAAUAUUGAAAGAGGUAGCAGGUGUCAGAUACUUUAGAAAAAUUGGGAGAAGAAACUUCACACUGCUAAUUUUGUUCUGUAACUUAUGUUAGUCACUCUGAUAUUGGGAAAGAACAUUAUUUUAGUAAUAGAACACCUUAGGUGAGCUAAAAUAAUACAAUGUUUCCAUGAGAGCAAAGUGUGACAACCUGAAUUGAGUGACCCUCUGACUGUUACCAUAGGCCACGUUUUACAAUUUUGGUUUUAUUUUAUAAGGAUAUGUUUUUCAGCAUAUAGACCUUUAUAAGGAACGUAACUUUACUUCAGAGUUUGGACUACCUUGGCAAAUUGUCCCAAAUGAUAUUUUAAAUAGUUUUAGGUUGUAUUUGAUAUGUUAUGCUUCUUGUUGGUAUUACAUGAAGAACACUGUGUAUUCUUUUACUUAUAUUCUUACCUCUUCUUUUUUUUUUAAUAUCAGAAUAAUAGCAUGUUUUUUAUUUUUAUUUUUUUUUGAGGCAGAGUCACACUCUGUCACCCGGGCUGGAUUGCAAUGGUGUGAUAGCAGCUCACUGCAGCCUCCGCCUCUCUGGUUCAAGUGGUUUCCUGCCUCAGCCUCCUGAGUAGCUGGGAUUACAGGAAUGCGCCACCAUGCCUAGGUAAUAUUUUUUGUGUUUUUAGUACUGAUGGGGUUUCACCAUGUUGGCCAAGCUGGUCUCGAUCGCCCGCCUUGGCUUCCCAAAGUGUUGGGAUUAUAAACGUGAGCCUCUGUGCCCUGCCUGGUUAUUUUUUAAAAAAAAACUGAGGAAAAUUUUCAAGUAUUUCUCUUGGAAGUACAAACCAACACUCCAUUCUUUGAAUCUCCGGAGUAAAAUUUGGGCUGAGCAGAUGCAGAGCCAAUUCCAUAGGCUGAUUCCUAGUUGAACAUGUAGAGUCAUAGAGGUAAUAGCUUUCAUAGGGACGUCUUUGAACUACUUUCUUUUUUUUUCUUUCUACUAAUAUUACUGAAAGCAGUUGUACGGUAGAGUAGGAUGGUGUUUAAUUUAUAGGAAGCAAAUCAGCUCACAUCUGUAAUUGCUGGUUCUGAUGUCAGUCCUAGUCUGCCUGGCCUACUCACUGCCAGAUCAGUUUCUUCUAUUCAGACCGAAGAUAUUUUAAGACCUCUGUCACCUACAACGGGAAGGAUCUGGAAUUAUUCUGGUGCCCUGAGCAUCCAUUGCUCACAAAGGAAAUACUGCCAGACUAGACUGAUGUCUAGUACAGGAAGUCCAUUACAGAGAAUGGUUGAUAUAAAGCAGAAAUUCAGAACCAGGAGAGUUUGGGGACAUGGAGCAGGCCAAAGUUGGAGAACUGGAAUUUGACCUGAAGGUGACACUGAUGAUAAAAAUCCAUCCAAGAAUUUAUAUGUGACAUCUGCAGCAGGUUCAAAUCUCUCAGCUAUGAGACAAACUGGAUACUUCCUAAGGAUUGCCAUCUAUUAUGCACAGAGAGCCAAAAUCCGUUACUGAAAUUGUCUGGGUGAGCCGCCUGCUGGGUCCAGUGAUGCACUGGUAGACAAAGGAGUUGAAAAAGAAGUGUGGCAUAUUCUUUGGAUGACUGGCAGAGUGUGACACCAGUAUGGCACCAAGCCCUACUAUGAUUCCAAGGACUUCAGGACUAAAAAUAUAUAUAUAUAUAAAUGAAAAAAAAUUUUGGUGGUAUUGGUUGGUGUGGUUGAAGUAAAUUUGAGCUUUACUUGGGGAAUGUGUAUUAUAUUAUCAUUCCAUAAUGUAAUUCCUUUGGUAAUCAAGCUUUAAAGAUCUUAUAUCUAUGAAACUCAUAUAGUUAUCACCUUUUAGUAUUGGGUUAUCUCACUGUAAGGGAAAUACAGUAAAGAAAAACAUCUGUUGACUAAAAGGGUUAAUUUCAGGACUAUGAUUUUCAUGUGGAAGUGUUUGCCUGGAGGAUUCUUGAAAUUUUGCCUUCAUCUAGAGUAUUUAAAAUGUUUCUAUUUGCAAAAAGCUAUUAUACUCAGAAUUUUCUAGGAAAACAUCCUUUUCAGUGGACUCUUCAAUAGUAAAGAGUCACACUGUAUGGUGUUAGUGUCCAUAGAACAGUUGAAUUCAUAAAUUAAUAUUUUUAGACCUAUCAACUAAAUUAAAUUCACUUAAAAUGAUUUGGCAAGCAGGUAUGAACUGAAAAUAAACCUAUGUAUUUUUGUUUUUUAGAAGUAUUGAAUCAGAAGAAAUUGGAACAUCAAAGUAUUCUCUGAACCAAAUUGAUGUUUUAUUUGGUUGAGAGUCCUUACUUUUGGUAUACUAUUUAUACCAGUAAUAGAGUAUUUGAAAGCAGUGCUGGGAAAUGAGGUGCAUGGAUUCUCUCAAUGUUGAAUCCCAUUUUUUUCCCUCAGUGAAUCUUCAACAUUUUUAAAUCUUAGCAUUCAACAAAAACUCUACAGCCUAGAUAUAAACCAUAGAUUACUUUUUAUAUAGCAUAUACAGUUCAUCAACAAACAGUAAAGUUUCCUUCAUGACUUACCUUGAAAUCUUUAUUCAAAGGAUAUACUAUUCAAUUUUUCAGUGUGCCACUGCCACCACUGCAUGUUUUUGGUCAGAGUGCAGUGCAACUAACAUCGCCAUCCUGCUAGGAAAAAGAUCUGCAGGUUGCUGGAUAGUGGAAGUUGCACACAUCUAAUUUACAAGUCAGAUUAGAGAUCAGAAUCUUACAAUAGCUUUAUGUGGAAUUGAUUUCAUUUCAUGGUUUUUAAGCUGUUUUUUCAUUGAAGCAAUGCCUGUAACUGAAAGACAGGUGUGUUGUAGCAUUUGAAUACCUUAAACUCUUUUGAAUCUGGAAUGAAAGGGAUGUUCUGGAUUCUAAAACUCAGAGAUUUUGAAUUAAAUGCCAUCAUUCAUUUAUUGUGCCAUAAUUGAACUACCUUGAGAACUGAAUUUGGAAUUACUGUGAUUAAUAUUUGGAAAGCUUUGCCAUUUUCAAAUACAAGUCACUUUAGGAAGGACCACAAUUUGUGUGUGUGUGUGUGUGUGUGUGUGUGUGUGUGUGUGUUUAUUUAAAUAGAGCAGCAGGCACCUUUUUACCUUAUAGAUAAGGUAAAUUUAAUAAGAAAUACGUGGUUUUUAACAUUGAUAUCCCAUUCUAUUUAAGAAGUCCAUUGUGGCCUUUCUGGAGGCCUUCAAUAAGGGGAAAGGGACGAUGAAUAGAACACUGUAGAUUGCAGUUUAUGUUUUUCCUUUUAAGGCAAACCAUUUUCAAAAUAUAAUAAUGCCAAUGAAUACAUAAAUAUAGAUUGAUAGUUUGAAGUUAUUUUAAGUUUACCUGUCUAUAUUAAAAUUGAGAGCCAUCUCAUAAGAGUGAGUAUAAAAAAGUUGUUCAUUUUAGAGUGCAUAGUGCCAUUUAAUUGAAUUAGAGAACACAGUUGCAAAAAAAAAGCAUCUUUUAGAUGGUUCUUGAGCCAUUAAUUGAUUUAUUGAAUAUAAUCAAGAAGAAAAAUCCAGAUGUUUAAAACUAGUUUUGUAUCAGGUCAGAAGAGUAUUUAGCUUUAUUCUCCUCCACUCCCUUGUCUGAUGAGUUCUCAUAAAUUGCUUUCUGAAAUGACAAAACAUUGGGAUUUGGAAAGCCUUGAGAAUUCAUCAGUUUUAUCUUUUUCUCCAGUGUUUUUUACAAAGGACCCAUUUAGUCGUGAUAUUUAUAGGAUAUGAGGAAGGCAGUGAUCCUGGCAUUCGUGGACUCCAGAAAACAUUUUGGAGAAAAAUUAAUGUAAGGUAAGGGUGUAGUAGGUAUACAUUGCUGUAUUCAUUUUAUUGUCCCUUCCUUCCUUCCUUCCUUCCUUCCUUCCUUCCUUCCUUCCUUCCUUCCAUCCUUCCUUCCUUCCUUCCCCUUGAAGAUCUUGUUGCAUACCAAUUUAUUCAUUUUAGUAUAGCAGUGACUAUUUAAAUGGGUCCCUUUCUAACCACCUUUCCCUCCAACCUCAAAAUCCCUGGUUAAAAUGCUUUUCUUUAAAGAGAGUCAGAGGUAAUUUUUUGAAUGGAGAAAGUGAGGCUAUUCCAGACAUUGGGAAAUGAGUGGAGUAUAAAAGGGAGAAUGAGAUCUAAAUGUGUUGUGAUAGAUAGUAAGAUCAUAGAUGAACACUCUAUUUUUGGAUUGAAAAGGGUGCUAGAGUAAGUAUAUCAAUGGAAUACAGUGGCUUGUUAUCAUUAUGAACUGUUUAGUAAGUCUCCAGUAUGCCAGACAUUGAGUAAGACAUUUUGCAUAAAUUCUGUCUUUCCAAAAUCUUGAAACAGGUGCAACUAUCCCAAUUUCCUUAUGAGGAAACAAGUUAAAUGGUGUAUACAAAGUCUUAGAGUAAGAAUUGAAAUAGAGAAUCAUACAGCUAGUGGCUCAUUUUGUGCAGAGACCUUUUCUUUCUGGUGAUUGUCUGAUAAGUUAUUAGUGAAUAGAAAAGAAAUCUGAAAGGCCAGCAUACAUGUAGGGAGAUUUUAAGAUUAACAGCUUUUAACACGAAUGACUUCAUGUUAGUGUUGUAGAAUGACAUUGGAGCCUUCUUGAGAAGCAGUGACAUAUUUGCGAAUAUUGUAUCUGGACACUAGAACUCAACCAUCUAAUGGGUUGCCUUUAUUAUUAGUAAAGUAUUGUAUAGCUGCACUUUCAGGUGUAAGUGAUGCCAUGGUACAAAACUCAUAUACGGAGGGCAGGUGAUCAUGAGCUACCAAAGAAACUGCUAUAUAUCAUAAGCUGAAUUGGAUCACCUCCAAAUAGAAUCUGUAGAAAAGUACUUGAAAGAGGACUGGUUCAAGCAGUCAUCUGAUACAAAGCUGACUACCAAACAUUUUGGGAUGCAGGGAUGAUAACUGGAUAAUGGUAUCAUGAAGCUCAUUAAAAUAAGAACUGUAAAUGUUUACAGGCUUUACAAGCAGAUAUAUGCAGCUCUGUAACAAAAUAUCAUCUUCUUGGAAAGGACCCAUUUGGUUAGGAACAAGGCCUUAGCAGCAGCGUUUUUUUUUUUUGAGAUAGGGUUUCACUCUGCCCAGGCUGGAGUGCAGUGAUGUGAACAUGGCUUACUGCAGCCUCAACCUCUGAGCUCAAGCAGUCCUCUCGUCCCAGCCUCAUGAGAAGCUGGGACCACAGGCAUGUGAUAAUACCCAGCUAAUUUUUUUAGUUUCUGUAGAGAUUAGGUCUCGCCAUGUUGCCUAGGCUAGCAUUUUUAAAUACAAAAGGCAACUGUGCAGUAGGGUGUUGGAGUCAGAUGAUCUGGUUAUGUUUUUUGAGAUAUAGAGCAAAAUGAUGUGGGAUAUUUGGCUUUGCUAUUUGUCCCCCAGGGGGAGUGAAGUAAAGCACAGCCAAGGUGAUAGUGUCAUGGCAGAGCUUAAAUGUGAGUACUGUGGCACCUUGGUGUGGGAUGUGGUAAUGAAGACAGGACAGGUAAAAAUGAAUGAAAUCAUGAACUCAAAAUGUUAGAGUGAAAAAUACUUUUCUAAUUGUUUGAAAAUACAGAAAAGUAAAAAGGCAAACAGAUCAUAGGCAAACAAAUAAGACAGUUGGACAGAGGUGAGAAGUAGGAGGGCUAUUCAAGAGUACAAUAGUCCUAGAAAGUUUUUCUCAAAGAGGGAGACGACUUGGAAAGAGAGAGCAGAAAAGUGAUUUAGAAAUAGAUGUUACUGAAAUAUGUGAGUGAGCUGCUCAAAGACUGCCAGGAGACAGAGAAAAUACUGGAUAAGAAGGAACAAGUGACCUUUAAUAUGAAGUUGUAUUUCUAUCUUAUGGUGGUCAAAGGUGACCAGCUAGUUCAGGUAAUGGCUUCCCAAGAAAAGACAUGCUGAUUGUUCCCAUUUGUUCUGGGAACAUUUAUGGAUAUUUCUAUAGGCUGGACUUAUCCUUGUAUCUUAUGAUACUGGGUGACUUGGAUUUCUGAUUUAGAAUCUGACUUAGGCUAUAAGUUUGUUAUGAUUAUUAUCCAUAUUAUUUUCAGCUUUUGGGCAAGAGAUUACACUUUAACUGGCUAUCCUUGCCAUCCUCGAGAAGUAAGGUAUCAGAUGUGACUUUAAAAAUUAACUUUAUGGGCCGGAUGCGAUGGCUCAUGCCUGUAAUCUCAGCCCUUUGGGAGGCUGAAGCGGGUGGAUUACCUGAGGUCGGAGUUUGAGACCAGCCUGGCCAAAAUGGUGAAACUCCAUCUCUAUUAAAAAUACCAAAAUUAGCCGGGGAUGGUGGUGCGUGCCUGUAAUUCCAGCUACUUGGGAAGCUGAGGCACAAGGAUCGCUUGAACCCUGGAGGUGGAGGUUGCAGUGAGCCGAGAUCACUCCACUGCACUCCAGCCUAGGCGACAGAGCAAGACCCUGUCUCAAAAUAAAUAAAUACAUAAAAAUUAAAAUUAACUUUAUGGAGUAUAAUUUAUGUCCAAUAAAGUGAACCAAUUUUUAAGUGAAUUUUGACAUGUGUGUACACCCAUGUUAACUAUCCCACUUUCAAAAAAUAGAACAGUUUAUCAUCCCUAAAAGUUCCGUUACGCACUGUUUCUAUUUAUUUAUUUAUUUGAGACGGAGUCUUACUCUGUCACCCAGGCUGGAGUGCGGUGGCACUAUCUCCACUCACUGCAAGCUUUGCCUCCCGGGUUCACGCCAUUCUCCUGCCUCAGCCUCCUGAGUAGCUGGGAUUACAGGUGCCCACCACCAUGCCCGGCUAAUUUUUUGUAUUUUUUAGUAGAGACGGAGUUUCACUGUGUUAGCCAGGAUGGUCUCGAUCUCCUGACCUCAUGAUCCGCCAGCCUUGGCCUCCCAAAGUGCUAGGAUUACAGGCUUCAGCCACUGCGUCUGGCCCCCUUAAUGCACUGUUUCUAUCAGGCCUUCCCUUUCCUCAUCUCCCCACAGACAGCUAGUGUUCUGAUUUCUAUUUCCAUAGAUUAGGUUAGCCUGUUCUUGAGCUUCAUAUAUAUGAGAUGAUAGAGUAUAUACCCUUUUGUAUCUGACUUCUUUUCCUCAACAUAAUGUUUUUGAGAUUAAUCCAUGUUGUUGCAUGUAUUAGUGGUUCAUUCUGUUUUGUUGCUGAGCAGUGUUUUAUUUUAUGUAAUUUGUUUACCAUUCUUCAGUUAAUGAGCAUUUGACUGUUUUUCUAUUUAUUGGCUCUUGCAAAUCAUAUCACUAUAAACAGAAUUUUUGUAUAAGUCAUUUUAUGAACAUGUAUUCCAUUUUCUCUGUGUUAAAUACCUGAGUGAAAUUAUUCUUUGAUAGGAUUGCUAUGUUUUAAUUUUAUAAUUAUAUAUAUAACUUUAUAUGUAUAACUUUUCCUAAAUGGUUAUACCCAUUUCUACCAUGCAUUGUUAGUUCAAGUUUGUAGAUGUCUGUAUUUUGUACCAAGAAUAUUGGUUUGUACUAAAUGAUUUUUACAAAGCCAGAGAGCCUGUAGGAGUAUUCUUCAUGUAAUAGCUGAAAUCUAGUAUAUUUUAAAGAUAUAUCUAUUUAAAAAAAAAAAACUCUAAUGAUAAUAAGAUUGAUUAAGUAUAUAUGAAAUUAUUGAUAAGUAGAUAUGCAGUUAUUGACCUGGUUGGUUGCACAGAAUUUUUCAUUUUCAUUUUGCAGGUAGCAUGUUUUAAUCUAAAUUCUAAUGUGGACAUUUUCCAUUGUAAACAGUUGGCUCUUCAUGAAAUGUAUAUAUAAUUAAAUAUGAAUAAUACUAAUCUUUAAGGUAAAAUUUGUAUGACCAGAUGAAGAAUCUCCUUUUUUCUUUUUCCUUGAUAUGUUUAGUCAGUAGCUUUCCCCCUCAUUUUUUUGUAAAUCUGUAUUUCACAUUGAGUUGCUUAAAAUGAGAGGUCUCAUAAUAGGUAAGUGGUAAAUGUAGGGGAAUUAUACACUUUUGAUAAUAGAAUGAUGACUAGGAAUUGUUUGUUUCAGUAUUUUUGCUAAAGCUCCAAAGCUGAAACCAAAGGGUAAUAAGUAACCCUGCUUUCUAAAGAGGGAUGUGGGGCUUAGUAAAAGAGAAUAGACUUGGUUCACCCUCAACACCUGUUUCCCGCAUAUAGGAGAAAUUAGAAGAGAGAUUAAAAGUGUCAUUCCGAUGGAGCUGUUAAUCUAGUGGGGAGUUAGUUUUGUGACAUUUCCCUGUUUCUCCCCAAAUGGACCUUUUUUUUCCAGCCCAGGAUUUGGAUUUGUCUGCCAGAAGUGUAAAUUGAUAUGUAGUUUGUCUGGAUGUUUAAUGAGCUGCAGAAUCUUGUUUCCUUGUGCUGCAGUGGCACCUUCCAGAGAGUUUUUGAGAAAACGUGAUCAUAGUCCCAUUUUCACACUGCUAUAAAGAAAUACCUGAGACUGGGUAAUUUAUAAAGAAAAGAGGUUUAAUUGACUCACAGUUCUGCAUGGCUGGGGAGGCCUCAGGAAACUUACAGUUAUGGUGGAAGGGGAAGUAGGCACAUCUUACAUGGUGGCUGGCGAGAGAGAAGGGUGAGUGAAGGAGGAACUUGCCAAACACUUGUAAACCAUCAGAUCUCAGGAGAACUCACUCACUAUCAUGAGAAUAGCAUGGGGGAAGCCACCCCAGUGAUCCAGUUACCUCCCACUGGGUUCCUCCCUUGACACCUGGGGAUUACAAUUACAAUGAGAUUUGGGUGGGGACACAAAGCCUAACCAUAUCACGUAACAUUUCUGAGAGUUGGGAGCACACUUGAACAUAGACUUGUUCCUGGAGGGGAGGAGAAUGACUGGCGUCAGUCGAGAUGGCAUGUUGAGUGAGAGAGCAGUAGGUAGAGGAGUCUGCAUGUGUCCAUCUUGUAUGGUUAAGAAGGCAUGACUUUUUUUGUCGUGCAAGUGGUCAUGGUGGGAGGUAACCAGACUUGAGUUAUCUGGAUGGAUCCUGCCAAGGAGGGCUGCUUGCCAUGUGAAGGGACUGUGGGCGGGAUAAUGGGAGGUUAGCCUAAGAGUGUAUUUCCCAGCUGGGUGUAGUGGCUCAUGCCUGCAUGCCUGUAAUUCCAGCACUUUGGGAGGCUGAGGCAGGAGGAUCACUUGAGCCCAGGAGUCUAUGGCCAGCCUGGGCAACAUAGUGAGACUCUUGUCUUUAUUCAAAAAAAAAAAAAAAAAAAGAAUGUAACUCCCACAAUAGGGGACUAUGAAAGAUGGAAGGGUCACCUUUUUGCUUGCUGUAACUGAUGACCCCUCUGCUGUGAAGUCACUUGAGAGUGACUGAGAAAUAAUGGAAUUUAUCUGGGGUUUUGAGAGAUGGGGAAGUGAGAUCCAGAGAAAUAUGUUUGAAAGCAUAUAUUCCAUUGAGUUCAGUUCACUUGACCAGUUUUUUAGUUCAAUAGGAUUUUUGUUCAGUUGAAUAAACCUUUAGUAAGUGCUUAAACAGAAUAUGUAAGGUACUGUUCUAGGCAUUUCAUGAAAGGCAAAGAUGGCUGUGGUGUUUUCUGUCCUCAGGGAGCUUCUGCUUUAGUGUAAAUAGCUGAAGUUAAUUCAUGGCAGAAUGACAUAGGUACUUUAAAUGUGUAAGUGGCAGUACUAUGGGAAUUUGGAAAGAACAGUGAAUACCACUGGGGUUCAGAGGAGUCUGUGGAGGAGGCCAACUUUGGGCUGGAUCUUGAAAGAACAAAAGGAUAUCAAGUAGGAAGAGAGGCAUUCUGGCAUGAGGGAAUAAACAAAGCCAUGGAAAUGGGUGACUGAGAAGUAAUUCUCAUUCACACUGGAAAAUGAUAAUUUUACUUUUUAAAUAAUGCUUUCAACCAUCAAUUAAGCUUGCUUGCCCAUGUUAUAAUUCCAGUUGAAUCUUGGUAUUUUUAUGUCAUCUUUGCAGUUCUCUAGUGAUGCGCAAUGUGUCUUCCUUUAUGAGCUAUAGCGUGCAUUAUCAAGUUGGAAACGUUACUCACUUUAGUACCUGGAUGGUUAUAAGCAUCAAAACCAAACUUCUAAGUCUAAUCACAAAGCCUAUUACUUUCCCUGAUUUAAAACAGUAAAAUGUAGAGAAGAUGAUGAUUUUUACAUAUCCUAAGAAGCACUUGGCAGAGCAAUUAGUUUCAUAACAAGUGAUUGUUUUUUAAAGCUCUCUCUAGAAUAAGAAUGAGUAUCUUGAUGCUAGUGUCACUUUUAAAUAGCUAUGGCUCCAGGAAUGUGUCUGUUCAUGUUAUUAUCUUAAAUACACACCUUAUCUAUCCAUAUUGCUAUACUUCAGAUGUGAAAGUGAAAAUAAAGGUGUGAAGUGCCUAGCAGACUUGUAUGGAUUUAUGUAAAUCAGAAAACACACAAACAAUCCAUUAGUCUCAGUGCUGAAGCCCUGAUAUAUUAAAAUCAAAUAUGGAUUAUUUCCUAAAAAUUUCACGUACACACAUACCAUCAUAUCCAGUGAUUUACUUGCCAAAAAAAAAAUCUUUAUUUCUUUGAACUCUAGACACAUAUCCAGCUGUCUUAUGACAUCUCCAUAUGGAUAUUUAAAGGAAUAUAAAUCUUCAAAUACUUAAAACUGAGCUGAUCUUUUUACCCAAACUUGUUUCAUCUUUAAUCUUCGCCAUCUAAGUCCAUUGGUGUUACUCAAACCAAAAACGUUGGAGUCAUCCCUGACUCUUCUUUUUCUUUCACAUUCACAGUUUGUCUCAGUAGUUCAUGUUAACUCUACCAUGAAAAUAUAUUUAGAAUUUGAAUCUUAUCACCUUUCACUCCCUCUACUACUACCUGGCCAAAGCCACUGUCAUUUCUUACUUGGAUUAUUUUAGUAGCCUCUUGACUGGUCUCUCAGCUUUUUCUCACAACCUGAAACCCAGCACAUCAGUCUGGUCUCAAUGCAGUAUCCAGAAUAUUUAGGUUAAAACAAGUUAAAUCCUGUCGUUCUUCAAAGCUUCAUUUGUUUUCUUUCUCACUUAAUGUAAAAGGUAAAGUCUUUGUAGUAGCUUAUAAGGCUGUAUAUGAUAUUGCCCCCUUUGCAACCUCUUUUUUGGACUCUCUACCUAACCUUCAUUCAUACCUCAGUUUUUGACUCCAUUUACUACCCCCCAUUCCUGUUUGACACCAUAUUGUUUCUGGAAUAGCUGGCCUUGGGGCUUUUGCGCUUGCUGUUCCCUCUGCCUGUAAUGUUCAUCCCCCAGGUGACUGCUUAACUUAUUCCCUAAUCUUUCUUGGGUCUUGAGAUGUUGCAUCUCUAGUGAGACCUUCUUUGGCCAUCUUAUUUAAAAUGUCCCUCUCCCUGCAACUACUUUAUGUUUCUCAUUUGCUCUUUGCCAGAUGAACUUACGUAUAUUUUGCUUUACUUUUUAUGACCUUUUUCUUUCAGAAUGAAAGCUUGAUGAGUGCAAAGUAUUUUAUGUUUUGUUUACUCCUGUGCCAUCAGACUUGGAGUCGUUUCUGGCACACAGUUGGCACUUAAUGCAUAAUUGAUUGAAUGAUAAAAGACAAUGAAAGAUUUAUUACCUAGGGGUUAAACCUGUAGUUAGGUUGAUUUGUCUUUUAUUGUAUCUUUGGGGAAUGAUGCUAUUUCCAAAUGGCUGAAUGUUACUUCUUUUUAAUUAAAUCAUAUUUAUUGGUAUAAUUUGCAUAUAGUAAAAUGUGCUUAUUUUAAAUGUACAAGUUAAUGUUUUGACAGAUUUACACAUUGAUGUAACUACUACUACAAUCAAGGUACAGAACAUCUCCAUCACUUCAAAAGUUUCCUUGUGUCUGUUUGUAGUCACUCCUCCCUCAUUCUCAUCUCCAGGCAACUAAUGAUCUGAUUUUUGUCACUGUGAAUUCGUUUUGCCUGCUCCAGAGUUUCAAAUAAAUAGAAUUAUACAUUAUAUACUCUUUAGAGCAUGAUGUUUUUGAGGCUUAUUAUGUUAUUGUAUGUGUCAUUAGUUUGUUCCUUUCAGUAAAGAAUAGUGUUCUAUUGUAUAAAUGUGCUCACAAUUUGCUUAUCCAUGUAUCUGUUCAUGAACAUUUGGGGCGUUUACAGGUUUUUUUGCCUAUAGUGAAUGACACUACCAUGAGCAUUCAAGGUGCGAGCCUUUGUGGAAAUAGGCUUUAAUUUUUCUGGGUUGAUUACUCAAUAGUAAAAUUACUGUUUUAUAUGGUAAGUUUAUGCUUAACUUUGUAAGAAAUUGCUUUGAAGAACUAUUUUCUUCAGUGAUUGUAUCAUACUCACUAGCAAUAUAUGAAAAAAUUCUAGUUGCUCCACAUUCUGGCCAGCACUUGGUAUAAUUCUUUUAAAUUCAGACACUCUAUUGGGUGUAUACUGGUAUCUCUUUGUGGUUUUAAUUUGCAUUUUUCUGAUUACCAGUGAUGUUGAUAUUUUCAUUUAUUCAUUGGCCAUUUAUAUAACUUCUUUUGUGAAAUAGCUGAUGAAAUCUUUUGUCCAUUAAAAAACGUUGGAUUGUUUCUUGUCAUUCAGUUACAAUAGUUCUUUAUAUCUUUGUAUAUCUAGAUACAAGUUCUUGUUAGAUGUUUUCUCUUGGUCUGUAGAGUAAGUGUAGUUUAUCAACAUUUUCUUUGGUGGUCUGUGCUUUCUUUCUUUCUUUUUUUUUGGUAAUAUCUAAGAAAUUGUUGUUGUUGUUUUUUUGAAAUGAAGUCUCGCUCUGUUGCCCAGUCAGGACUGGGAUUACAGGCGUGAGCCACCGCGUCCGGCAAAUGUCUAAGAAAUCUUUGAUUAAUACCAGGUUGUAAAAGAUUUUCUGUGUUUUCUCCCAAGAGUUUUACAGUUUUGGCUUUUACAUUAGGUCUCUGAUUUGUUUUGAGUUAAUUUUUAUAUAUAGUGUGCGGUAAGGAUCAAGGUUUGUUCUCUUCUAUAUCCACCUGUUCUUUUCCUUUGAAUUACCUUGAAAUUUUGUUAAAAAUCAACUAAUCAUGGCCAGGCAUGGUGGCUCACGCCUGUAAUCCCAGCACUUUGGGAGGCUGAGGUGGGUGGAUCACAAGGUCAGGAGUUAAGACCAACCUGGCUAACAUAGUGAAACCCCGUCUGUACUAAAAAUACAAAAAAUUAGCCUGCUGUGGUGGCGGGCACCUGUAAUCCCAGCUACUCGGGAGGCUGAGGCAGGAGAAUCGCUUGAACCUGGGAGGCAGAGGCUGUGGUGAGCUGAGAUUGUGCCACUGCACUCCAGCCCAGGUGACAGUGCGAGACUCUGUCUCAAAAAAAAAAAAAAAAAAAAAACAACCAAUCAUAUAUGUGUGGGUUUUUUCCUGGGUGCUGUUAUAUUGAUCUAUAUGUCUAUCAUGCCAACAUAACACUGUUUGUUCAGUAGUAAGUCUUGAAAUCACAUGGUUUAAGUUCUUUUUGUUCUUUUUUGAAAUUGUUUUCACUAUUCUAAGUCUUUUCUAUUUCCAUAUCAAUUAGAGAAUCGGCUUGUACAUUUCUACAAAAUACUUCUGGGAAUUUUAAUUUCCAUUGUGUGAAUUCAGUGGAUUGGUUGGGGAGCAUUAACAUCUAAAUGAUUGAAUUAUUCUAAACCAUGAAUAUAGUAUACCUCAAUUUAGUUAUUCUUUCAUUUCUCUGAGUAAUGUUUUGUAGUUUUCAGUGUGCUAAUCUCUUGUGUCUUUUAUUAAAUUUGUCCUAGGUGAAUAGGACGUGAAUUAUAUUUCUGAAUGCCAUUGAAAAUGCUAUUUAAAAAAUUUACAGUUUGUCAUUGUUUCUAUACAGAACUAGAAUUGAUUUUUACAUAUUGAACCUUGAUAAUGUAAUCAUUAAUGCUUUUGACUUUUUUUGUGUGAAUUCCUCAGGAUGCUCUCUAUAUAUGAUCUUGUUAAUCACAAAUAAAGACAGUUACUCCUAUCCAAUAUUAGUGUCUGUUACUUCUCUUUUUCUACAGCACAGAUGAGGACAGUGUUAAAGCACAGAGUAGGACACUGUUUACAUUGCACAGACUAGUGCAGUGUUAAAUAGAAGCGGUGAGAGUGAACAUCCUUGCCUUGUUUCUAAUCCCAGGGAGGAAGCAUUCAGACUUUCACUGUUACGUGUGAUAUUAGCUCUAAGUUUUUUGCAGAUGUACCAUAUCAGGUAGAGCAAGUUCCCUUUUAUUUUAAGUAUACUGAAAGCUUUUAUUAUAUUGCAUGUGAAUGUUGAAUGUUUUCAUAUUUUUUUUUGCCAUCUAUAGGGUGAAUCAUUUGUAUUUUCUUUUUUUUUUUUUUAAUUGUUUUUUUUUUUUUUUUUUUUUUUUAAGACGGAGUCUCGCUCUGUCACCAGGCUGGAGUGCAGUGGCACGAUCUCGGCUCACUGCAAUCUCUGCCUUCCGGGUUCAAGUGAUUCCCCUGCCUCAGCCUCCCCAGUAGCUGGGACUACAGGCGUGCACCACCACGCCCAGCUAAUUUUUGUGUUUUUAGUAGAGACGGGGGUUUCACCAUGUUGGUCAGGCUGGUCUCGAACUCCUGACCUGGUGAUCCACCCGCCUCAGCCUCCCAAAGUGCUGGGAUUACAGGCCUGAGCCACCGCGCCCAGCCAUUUGUAUUUUCUUUUAACACUUGUUAAUAUGGUGAAUUGAAUUGAUUAGAUUUUGAAUCUUAAACCUGUCUUUGCAUUUUUAUGAUAAACUCCAUUUUUUCAUGGAGUUUUAUGUUAUCUAUGGAGGAUAUAUUCUUUUACUAUGCAAAAUUUGAUUUGCUUAAUUGCGUUGUUGAUUUGUGGAUGUGUGUUUAUGAGACCUAUUAGCUUUUUUUUUCUGGGGGGCUCUUAUGGACUGUGUGUGUUCCCUCAAAAUUUUUAGGUUGACGUGCUAACUCACAAUGGUAUUCAGAACUGAGGCCUUUGAGAAGUAAUUAAGUUUAGGUGAGGUCAUGAGGGUGGGGCCCUCUUAGAAGAAGAAGGAAAAACUAGAGUUCACUCUUUCUCUUUGAUGGGAGUACAGUGAGAAGGCAGCCAUCUACAAGUGAGGAAGAAGGCCCUCACCAGCUAACUGAAUAGGCUGGCAUUUCGAUCAUCCCAGCCUCCAGAACUGUGAGAAAUAAAUUCCUGUUAUUUGAGCCACCCAGUCUAUAUCGUAUUUUGUUAUAGAAACCUGAGCUGACUAACCCGGGAGUAGGGUUGUAAUGUCUUUGUCAGAUUUUGGUAUAAAGGUCAUGAUUGUUUCAGUAGAUGCAGAAAAAGCAUUUGACAAAAUCUGACACUUUUUUUAGUGAUAAAAUACUCUAAGAAUAAAAAGGAAAUUUCCUCAACAUGGGAAAGGGCAUCUAUGUAAAAACCACAGCCAACAUCUUAAUGGUGAAAGAGGAACAGAGCAAGAAUGUUGCUUUCACUAUUCAGUUUUGUAUUGGACAUUCUAGCCAAGACAAUUUGUCGAGAAAAAGAAAUAAAGGCAUCCAGAUGGGAAAGAAGUAAAACUAUCUCUAUUUGUAGAUGACAUGAUCUUCUAUAUAGAAAAUCCUAAGGAAUCACCAAAAUGUAUUAGAAUUCAUAAAUGAGAUCAACAAGCUUGCAAGGUAUAAUAGCAAUAUACAGAAAUCAAUUGUAUUUCUAUACAUUAGCAGUGAACAAAAAUGAAAUUAAGAAUUCCAUUUAUAAUUGCAUCUAGAAAUUAAGAAAAUAAGCGGUAAAAAAAUGGUACUCUGAAACCUACCAAAAAUUAUUGAAAGAAAUUAAAGAAUUAGACAUCCCAUGUUCAUGGAUCUAGAUGACUUAAUAUUGUUAAGAUGUCAGUAUUAUCCCAAAUGAUCUACAGAUUCAAGGCAAUCUCAGCUGCCAUUUUUCUUCUUCAGAAAAGGCAAAGCUGAUCCUAAAAGUUACAUGGAAAUUCAGGGUAGUCAGAAUUUUUAAAACAGCUUUGAAAAAGAACAACAAAAGUGAAGGAGUCACAGUUCUUGAUUUCAAAACUUAAUACAAAGCUACAGUACCCAAAACAGGGCGAUACUGGUAUAAUGAUAGACAUAUAGGUCACUGGAAUAUAAUUGAAAGCCCAGAAUUAAACCCUGACUUUUAUGUUCAAUUGAUUUUUAAAGGGUGUCAUGACAAUUUAAUAAAGAAAGAAUAGUCUUUUCAACAGAUGGUGCUGGGAUAACUGUGUAUCCACUAGCAAAAGAAUAAAGUUGGACCCCUUUCAUGUACUAUAUAUUAAAAUAUUAAUGCCAAAUGGAUUAUGGACCCAAAUGAAAGAACUAAAACUAUAAACUCUUAAAAGAAAACAUAAGAGUAAGUCUACUUGUUCUUGGGUUAGUCAAAGCCUUUUUACAAGACACCAAAAGCACAAGUGACAGUAGAAAAAAUAAAUAUGUUGGACUUCAUCAAAAUUAAAAACUUUAUACUUUAAAAGACACUAUCAAAAAUAAAGUGAAAAAAACCAACACACAACAUGCAAGAACAUAUUUGUCAGUUAUAUUUGUGAUAAGGGACUUGUAUCCACAAUAUAUAAAGAACUGUUACAAUUCAAUAAUCAAGACAAUUCAAAAAUAUGAAAAGUAUCUGAAUAGAAAUUUUCCAACAGACAGUAGGCAUAUGCAUAGAUGCUCUCAGUGUCAUUUACUGUUGUGAAAUGCAAGUCAAAUCAGAAUUUCUCAUCUGCGUCUUUGUAUUUUAAAUUAUAAAUAAAGUUUAUAUUUACCUCUGGAAGUUCUACUUUUUAAAAUAGCUUUUAUUUAUUAUUAUGUUACAUUUAGAAAUAAAUUCUUCUGUAAUCCCAGCACUUUGGGAGGCUGAGGUGGGAGGCCUACUUGAGGCCAGGAGUACAAGACCAGCCUGGCGAAUAUAGUGAGAUCCUGUUUCUAUUAAAAUAAUUAUUAAAUACAUUGUCAAGUACUGUUUUAGUAUAUUCAUUGUUUAGUGUACUUGCUAUCCUGGUAUGUUUGUUCCAUCAUAUCUGUUAUUUCUGGAUCUAUUUUUUAUUGACUGAUUUUUGUCUUAGUUAUGAGUCACAUUUUUCUUCUUUGUAUGUCUGGUAAUUUUUGGUUUGCUGAUGGGGAUUGUAAAUGUUGCAUUAUUGAAUGUCUUGAUUUUACUGUCUUUUAAAAAAGAGUUUCAGUUUUAGCAGGCAGUUUACGUUCUUUGUGAAUCAGCUUGAUCUUUUUGGGGCUAGUUUUGUUUGUUAGGAUUGUUUUGAGUAUCCUUUACUAUAGAGGAGGUAAAUUAAUAGAGGAGGUAAACUAUACAGAGGUAAAUUAAUCUUAUUUCUAAGGUGUGAUUCUUCUUUAUCCUCUGCUGAAUGCUGUGCAUGGUCAACGAAGUCCGUCUACUCUUCUAUUCCAAAUCUGCCUGUCUUCCAGGCUUCUGUGACCUUUUGGAAGUGUUGUUAUUGUUCUCUCAUAUUUGUUCUUUUACCAGUCUCAUGGAAUCUUAGAAUAUUCCUCAGAAGAGUACACAUGGAACCCUUGUGUAGACAUGUGGUGCUUUCCCUCUUCUUAGCUCCUUUUACGUAUGUACUGUACACUUAUAAACUUAAGCUACCUCAGGCUUCCUAAAACUCUGAUAUCUGUUCCCGCGAUUCAGCUGAACCACCAUGUACUUAGUGUCUCCCACCAUGAUGCAGAGAGUGCCUCCAGGCAGAAAGCUGGUGCAAUCAUAGGGUUUCCCUUUCUUUUAGGGAUCAUAGUUCAUUGCUGCCAUUAUUGUCUACUGUCUGAAAAUGAUUGUUUUGUAUGUUUAUCAAAUUUUCUGGUUGAUUAUGGUAUGAAGUGGGCAAGCCUGGUGCUAGUUAAUCAAAGCCAGUAUUGGAAAUGCCCUGUUACUCCCUUUUUAGUAUUGAAAUUUAAGAAAAAAAUAAAAGUUUUUGCAUGUAUCUAAGUGUUUUAUUUAUACAUAUCUCAUCACAAAAAAUUGUUGAACAUUUUCCACCCUUUUCUUGAUGACUUCUCUUUUAAUUAUUUUAUGAUGCAGACUUAUGUGCUUUAGACUUUUGAAAAUACUCCUCUCCUAGUUUUCCUAAUUUAUCUUUUCCUCCUCCAGUAUUUUGUCCAUAUUGAGGCCAAUUUCAGUUUUCAGUGGCUCCCUUAUUCCCUGAAACAACCUUUUUUUAAAUAAAUCAUCUUCAUUAUUCACAAAAGGAGGUUUUAAUAUUUAACCUUGGUACUUAAGGGCCUGUCCAGUAAGUCUCCUGUCUGCAUAUUCUACGUUUUUAUACUUAACAUAGUACUUCACUGCCUUGGCCAGCAUUACUUUACUAGCCUCUGUUUCUUUGGUAAUACCGUUUCCUUUGCUGAAAGCCUAUCUUCAGUGCUCUCUGUGAAAAGCUUCACCAUUCUUCAAAGUCUCUCAUUUCUUUAUUGUGGUGCUUUUCUUUUCUUUUUUUUUGGAGAUGAGUUUCGCUCUGUCUCUGUCACCCAGGCUGGAAUGCAAUGGUGCGAUCUCUGCUCACUGCAACCUCCGCCUUCCGGGUUCAAGCAAUUCUCCUUCCUCAGCCUCCUGAGUAGCUGGCAUUACAGGUGUGCACAACCAUGCCUGGCUAAUUUUUGUAUUUUUAGUACAGACAGGGUUUCACCAUGGUGGCCAGGCUGGUCUCGAACUCCUGACCUCAAGUGAUCCCCCCCGCCUCGGCCUCCCAAAGUGCUAGGAUUACAGGCCUGAGCCACCAUGCCCGGCACUGUGCUUUUCUUACUAGGAUCUAGUUACUGGUUACAGAUACUAGUUUUCUUACUAGGUUAUAGUUCUUGAAUAUUUGUCAAAUACUCCUUACUACUUUGUAAGCCCAUCAAAUGCUGUACUCAUCUUUGAUUCUGCCAUAGGCCGGUGUUCUGACUGGCCUAGAAGUUGGCGCAUAGUUGAUGUUCUGUAAAUACCUAUUGAAUAUUGACUGAAACAGCCUUUAAAAUAGAAAUUAUAGAUAAAUUUGGCAGGUGUAUCCUGAUCUUCCGUGUGGCUUUUUGAGGUAAUAAGUUUAUGGUACGAGUGCACUGUCUAAGUAUCAUGCUCUCCUAAGAUACACCUUUCUGUAUGGCUGUAAUUCUAAGUUAGGGAACAGAUAGAAAUAAAGGGUCUGUUCAUUUCAUCUGUGUAGUGUUCAGUAAAGACAGGGAGAUUGCUAUGGGCAAUCUAUUGGUUACCCCACUUGUUCUCCAGUGUAAUCGAUAUCUUUCUUUUUACUUAUUUUAUGACUCUUCUAGCUUAAUAUCUUUUAGUCCACAGACAUAUAUGUGUGAGUAUAUAUAUGUAUAUAAUUAUAUAUAUAUAUAAUUGAGGAAAAGCAGUAUUUGUGGUGGCAUGGGGUAAACACAAGUAAGCCCUCAAUGACUUUGGUAGACAGAUAUUUUCUGUAUGCCCUAAGUGUGGAGAUGAGUGCCAUUGUAGGUAGAGGAGGAGCACUUGGAUGUGUGGUGGCCCCUUAAGGUUCUCAGAGGCUUAUAGCUAGGUGUGUAAGUCAGGGAGGGCCAAAUGUGCUUUGCCUAGCACAACUUUCACUGACUGAGCAGUCUAUUUUCAGAUAGUCCUUCAGAUAAUGAAAGUUGUCAUUGCUUAAUUUUAUACACUCUUCCACUUAUUUAUACCUACUGCCAUUUACUGAGGUCAUCCCUUCAAAAAAUAUUUCUUGAGGACCCAUGAUGUGCCCGUGCUGGCACUGAAAAGAUAAAGAAGACAUGCCUCCUGGAGGAGUGGCAGUGGCCUUCAGAGGUCUUGAUUAGUGCUUUGAGGCCACUGUUUGUGGAACCUGGCGUUUAAUACUUGCAUUUCCUCCAGAAAGCAUGUGGGCAUUGGUAGUGGAUGUGCUUUUAAAAAGAGCCUCUUAUGGCUGUAUUUUGUACAUGAUCCCGUGUUUAAUAAGAUGGAUGAUUCAGUUUCUUCUGUGAAUUCAGGUUGUGAUAUUUGCAUCUUUGGAAAUGCUAUUUAGGAAAUAAAUACCAGCAUGGAAAUUCAUAGUUUGUUAAUUUUCUUGAAGCUACAAGGCCUGGUGCGGUGGCUCAUGCCUGUAAUCCCAGCACUCUGGGAGGCCGAGAUGGGUGAAUCACCUGAGGUCAGGAGUUUGAGACCAGCCAGGCCAACUAGGCGAAACUCUGUCUCUACUAAAAGUACAAAAAGUAGCUGGGCGUGGUGGUGCGCAUCUGUAGUCCCAGCUACUCAAGAGGCUGAGGCAGGAGAAUCACUUGCAUCUGGGAAGCGGAGGUUGCAGUAAGCUGAGAUCAUGCUACUGCACUCCAGCCUGGGUAACAGAGCGAGAUUCUGUCUCAAAACAAACAAACAAACAAAAAAACAAGACAAAACAAAAAAGGUACAUCUUUUUUACUAAGUUGCAUAGCUGUGGUAUUUUGUGUAAUGGUAAUUGAAAUGUAAAAAAUGGUUUAUUGGAAGGAUUUUUGGUUUUAAUCAGAUUUUUUUAAAUAAAGAUUAAAACAUUGGCAUUGCAAUUGGCUAGGAAAAAAACCCAUUUUCUUUCUUUUUUUCAAUGUACUAGCCUUUGGUAAACAGAUGGUCAGAUUAAAUGCUAUAUAAUUGAAAGUGCCUCAGAGUAAAAACUUGCAGAUAUUUGGGAAAGGAAAUAUAGUUAAUACCAAAAAAUUUUGGGGGCUUCUGGUUCACAAAUUUGCAUUACUCAUCCUCCUUAGCUGAUAACAUAUAAUCAUCAAGAGGCUGGACAAGACCAUUUUCUCGUUUUGAGUUAUUAUUUUUUUUCCUUUAACCCCUAUCCCUACCCCUGUUUUCCACCCCUAUCCCAGCUUCCCUUAGUAGACCUUGACUUGCAUGUGUUUGGCAUAUUACCUUGGAUUGGCACAUAUCUUUGAAAAAUACAGAACAGUUCGUAUAUUAUGUAUAUCUUAAAUUCAGACCUCAAGCUUUCUUUUUUCACUUUUGACACUGUUUUUAGUUUAGACAUGUUAUGGUGUAUAUCUCUAGCUAAAUACUUCUAAACAUAGUUUGGUUCCUUUGUAAGUUAUCCAGGUAAUGGAUGAAUGGAUUGCUUCUAAAACCACUUAGACAUAAUGCUGUGAUAAACAUCUGUACACAAUUUUAAUACUAGUUUUAUGUGUAAGUUCUUUGGGCUGUGUAUUUAGGAGUGGGAUUGUUGGAUAUAGGAUAGUGGCUUGCAAUAGCAUUUUUCCCCGCUUGUUCAUUUAUAUUUUUCUCAUACAAUUUGUAUAUCAUUUGGCCAUUUAAUUAUAGAUAAUUAAAAAAAAUAGUUUUUACUGUGGUAAAAUGGACCUAACAUAAAAUUUACUAUUUUUACCAUUUUUAAGUGUAUAGGUCAGUGGCAUUAGGUACAUUCCCAUUGUUGUGCAGCCAUCUCUACCAUCUUUAUCCAAAGCUUUUCACCUUCCUCAACUGAAACUGUACCCAUUAGGCAGUGGGUACUCACUCCCCAGGCAACCUGGCAGUCCGUGGCAGACUUUGUCUUUAUGAAUGAGACUACUCUAGGUACCUCAUAUAAGUUGAAUCAUACGGCAUUUGCCAUUUUGAUUGACUAGUUUAUUUUACUUAGUAUAAUGUCUUCAAGGUUCAUUCAUGUUGUAGCAUAUGUCAGAAUGUUUUUCCUUUUUAAGGCUGAAUAAUAUUACAUUGUAUAUACAUAUACCACAUUUUAUUUCUCCAUUCGUCCACUGAUGGACUCUUCUACUUUUUGGCUGUUGUGAGCAAUGCUACUAUGAAUGUAGGUAUACAAAUAAUCUGUUCAAGUCCCUGAUUUCAAUUCUUUUGAGAUGUAUACCCAGAAGUGGAAUUGCUGGAUCAUAGUUUUAUUUUUUGAAGAACUGCUAUACUCUUUUCCAUAGUGGCUGCACCAUUUUGUAUUCCCACCAGCAGUGUACACGGAUUUCAAUUUCUCCAUAUUCUUACCAACACUUGUUUUUAAAUUUUUAAAAAAUUAAAAAAGAGAACUCUAUAUUACAGUAGUAGCUAGCAUUAAGUAAGGGCUUACUGUGAGCCCAAGUGCUGUUCUGUAAGUUUUACAUGUGAGAAACUUUUAGCCUUCACAACAGGUUUCCAAAAUAUAUAUAUAGAGAAUACGCCAUUAAUAGAGUUCCUCGGAUAACAGAGUGAUACACUGGAACUUUGAAUUGAGGCACCAGUAUUCAACACAUGCUUCUAUAUCCAAAGGAAGUGCUAGACCAUAUACAGAAUUAUAGAAAGCUGGUUUUGUGACAUUUGAAUCCCUUUACUCACAUAGAGGCUAUCAAAGUGGGGGUGUUGGGGGGGAAGAUUUUGUUAGAUGAAUUUUUCUGCAGGUCAUCAGAGUGCUGUAUGUUUUACCCUUGUCUCCCACAAGUUAGGGGUCUCUGAAUCUUUUGUCAAGUCUAGUGAGAGAAGUUUCAACUAAACUUUAUCUUGGGGUCACAGGAUAUUGAUGCUUGACUCAUACCUGGGAAAGCUGAAGUGUUCUAUAGCAGUAGUGCUGGGUUUGAGAAGUAAUUGCACUCUUCUCUGUCAACAGGGAAAUCAACCUGCUCUCAUUUUUAAGGGGAUCCUGCUGAAAAAAAAGUCUCCUGCCAGGGCAAGAAGAUCCCAGCAGUAAUGGGCUGUUUGUGUACCACCAGGGGUUAGAAGCUAAGGAGGCAUUAAGAGCUUUUAGCAGAGAGAGAGAGCAGUGUCUCUGGCAGGAUAUUUGCAAUUGGAGGAGUAUACCAUUGGAAGAGUGCACAUAAGCUCCCCAAGAGAGGAAGAAUUAGCGUUAAACACUCUGCCAUAUCCCCUCUGCCAUAGCCCUAGAUCAUUUUGCUACAGAUAGCAAUCAAGAACUGUCUUAUAUGCCUGACCUCUCCUCCCUUUCCUGACCUUGAUCCUGGUGGGCUCAGAAAACUCAGGAAGAUGGUGGAAGAGAAAUUUGGUGAGAUGAGGAGGAUCCUGUUCCUUCCUUCACUGACAGUGGCUGGUGCUGGGCAGGCCCCAGCUGAGUGAAGAACAUAGAUUUAAUGUUACAUGUACUUUGGAGUUUUGAUUGUUAUUUGGGUCUAGUCUUUUUAUUUUGUAAAAUUUCAAGCCUAUUGGAAUGUUGAAACAAUACAAUACAAUAAACACCCCAUACCUUUUACCAGUUAUUAACAUUUAGCCACGGUAUAUAUUGUAUUUAUACUCUUUUGGGCAGUGGGAUGGGGCUGAACCAUUCAAAAGUGACGUUUUACCCCUUCAGCUUGUUUAUCUUAAGAAUUAAAAUAUUCUCUCUCUGGGCGCGGUGGCUCACGCCUGUAAAUCCAGCACUUUGGGAGGCCAAGGCAGGCGGAUCAUGAGGUCAGGAGAUCGAGACCAUCCUGGCUAACACAGUGAUACCCCAUCUCUACUAAAAAUACAAAAAAUUAGCUGGGUGUGGUGGCAGGCGCCUGUAGUCCCAGCUACUCGGGAGGCUGAGGCAGGAGAAUGGCGUGAACCUGGGAGGCGCAGCUUGAAGUGAGCCGAGAUCGCGCCAUUGCACUCCAGCCUGGGCGACAGAGCGAGACUCCAUCUCAAAAAAAAAAAAAAUUAAAAUAUUCUUCUAUGUAGUCGUAAUACUUUUACCACACCGAGGUCUUUACCAUUGGUAUAAUAAUGUAUACUAUACAGUCUAUAUUCAAUUUUCCCUAAUGAUCUAAGACUUUUUUUUUCUUUUUUAAGAGAUGGAAUCCAGCCCGGCACUGUGGCUCACACCUGUAAUCCCAGCACUUUGGGAGGCCGAGGACUUGCUGGAGAUAUAGAAAGGGACCUGACACAGUUUCUGGCCUUAAGGAGCUCUCAUUCCAGUGGGGAAGAAAAAAACUAAAAUAAUGAUGUCCGAGAGCAUCAGAAAAGAACCUGCUCUGGUCAGGUAUCUCUGCAUUAGCCAGAUUGGACAUAUGUAAAGGGACAUCAGUAUAUCUGGAUCAUCAGUGGUAUAAUGUGUUAUAGAGGUGGACAAGCCUGCAGAUUGAAGUGGGGAUCGUCCAGAUUGUUCCCUUCCCUGGACCAUAUGGGUUUCAGGAAAAAGAAUGUAGCAUUGUUCUGUUUUACAGAGGAAGCCUCUACCUGUGACUGAUGAUUGUGCUUCAAGAAGACCAUAGGGAAGAACGCAUUUUCAUCUUGCUGCAAAAGUUGCAAUAGAACCUCCCACAUGCUUAGUGUUCAGUUCUGCCUACUGAGCGUCUUGAAUCUAUAGGAGCAUCUACAUGUACUGCCUCCAUAGUGGCUGAUAAUUUGCAGAUAACUCGUGAACCAGACCCAUAAGAAACAUCAUGAUAUGUACUUUAGAUUAAUCAUGGAAAAGGACAAGAUGAUGAAGAAUCAGAAAGCAGUUUUCUUUUCCAAUAUUUAUAUUGCUUUCUUUGAGUUACUUUCUAGCAAUUUCCAUCAUUUGAAGGAUUAAUGGCUACCACUUUGUUGAACCUAGAGGGUGUCUGUGAACUUAUUGAACACUACCUUAUUAGAGCAGAAGUCUCCAGUGGACCAUGAACUCUGCAUGGCUGGGACUCUGAACUUACCUCUUACUCACAAAACCUGCAGGGCUCUCAAAUUAAUGUUUAAAAUGCAAGCUACUGACAAGGAAUGGGAUCUGAAGGUUUGAAUGGGCCAAUGAGUAUCCUCAUCAUUGAAGCAUUCUAUGGAGGCUCCCAUAAACAGCUGGUGGAUCUUCUUCAAGAAGAGUUAGGAGACUGUGUCGUUUAUACCCUUCCUGCAAAGAAAUGGCAUUGGAGAGCCCGGACAUCUGCUUUAUAUUUCUCUCAGACCAUUCCCAUCAGUGAGCAUUACAGGACCCUCUUUGCAAGUUCAGUGCUUAACCUGACCGAACUGGCUGCCCUUCGGCCUGACCUUGGGAAACUGAAAAAGAUUCUGUAUUUUCACGAGAACCAGUUGAUAUAUCCUGUCAAGAAAUGUCAGGAGAGGGAUUUCCAAUAUGGAUACAACCAAAUUCUUUCAUGCCUGGUGGCUGAUGUGGUUGUAUUCAACUCAGUUUUUAAUAUGGAAUCAUUUCUCACUUCCAUGGGAAAAUUUAUGAAGCUGAUUCCUGAUCACAGACCCAAGGAUCUGGAAAGCAUCAUCAGACCCAAGUGCCAAGUUAUUUACUUUCCCAUCAGGUUUCCUGAUGUGAGCAGCACCUCCACCAGAGUUGGAACUGGGAAAGAGAAAGGAAGUGUUCAGACAUGUGCCUAUUUGCAUAGUCACGUCAUUGAAUUAAUGCCAGGACAGCACAAACAUUCUGUCCAGUUCUAUAGAAAAGCCAGUUUCACCCCAUCAGUAAGAUUCAUGCCCAAGCACAAAACAACCCAUUUAAAGAAGAUGCUCGGCCUUAAAGGAAAUGGCGGUGCGGUUCUGUCCAUGGCCCUUCCUUUUCAGCCAGAGCAGAGAGAUUCAGAGGAUUUAUUGAAGAAUUUUAAUUCAGAGUGUGAUACACACUGUGGCCUUGAUACUGCACGACAAGAAUAUUUGGGUAACUCAUUAAGACAGGAAUCAGACUUGAAAAAAUCCACCUCGUCAGAUAAUUCAAGCUCUCAUCAUGGUGAAAAUAAACAAAAUCUGACUGUUGAUCCCUGUGACAUUUUGGGUGGAGUUGAUAAUCAGCAAAGACUGCUACACAUUGUCUGGCCUCACAGGUGGGAGCAUGAUAAAGAUCCAGAAAGCUUUUUUAAGGUAUUAAUGCAUCUUAAAGACUUAGGACUCAAUUUCCACGUGUCUGUACUUGGAGAAACCUUCACAGAUGUCCCAGAUAUUUUUUCAGAGGCCAAAAAGGCAUUGGGAUCUUCUGUCUUACACUGGGGCUACUUACCCAGCAAAGAUGACUAUUUCCAAGUACUGUGCAUGGCUGAUGUUGUCAUCUCAACAGCUAAGCAUGAAUUCUUUGGAGUGGCAAUGUUGGAAGCUGUGUACUGUGGGUGUUACCCACUUUGUCCUAAAGAUUUGGUUUAUCCCGAAAUAUUUCCAGCUGAAUAUCUGUAUUCUACACCUGAACAGCUUUCAAAAAGGCUCCAGAAUUUCUGCAAGAGACCAGAUAUUAUAAGAAAACAUCUCUAUAAGGGUGAAAUCGCUCCGUUUUCUUGGGCAGCCCUACAUGGUAAAUUCAGGUCUCUGCUUACAACAGAACCUAGGGAAGAUUUGUGACAGAUGGGGCUAAGUCACAAACUUGCAGCCUAAGGCAGAAUCUGAAGAACUUUCCAGAGUGUGCCCAUAUUUACCUGAUCAGAGAGAAAAGAAAAUCUGCAGAGGAAGCUGAGCCUGGCUGCUUGUCAUAGCUGACACAGAGCCAUCUGCCACAAACCUGUGGCGGCUUCAGAUCUCCAAUCCCUGCCACCACCCCAACUCAAAUUAAAUACAGAUUCCUAGAGACGUUAUGAUGGUUACACAUGUCCUCGGCAUCACAUGUAGGAGACUGUUCAAAAAAAAUAUGUGGCCUGUUGUAUAACCGCACUCAUGUAUCCCAUAUGUGGUGCCACAUUGAAUUUCCGGUUGAAUCCGUUUUUAUCCUUUGUACUGGAUGACAUGGUGCCUGAAUUCUUUCUUUUCGCCGACACGAUGGCAGCCAAACUGCAGCUUCAAACGCUCACACUUGGCUGGGUUUCUACCUAGGUUGCCAGGUUAUCAUCGGAGCCUUCUUGUGUCCUCAAAGGGCCACGAGGCCUGAAAGGAGGAUCAGAAUGCUUUGGGAUUAAUUGGGCAGCCAUCGCAGAAUUGUUUGUGGGCAAAGGGCUGCUUUAGCACUUUUCUUUUAGCAAAUUAAUGACUCUCAGGCACAGGGGGUUUUAAGUGAAGGUAUUAAUAAGAGGUCUGGCAGGUAUUCCCAUGAUUCACAGAGUUACAUUUGCAUUUAAUUAAUCUUAAAGUUGCAAGAUAAACAGCUGUAAUUCGGACAAACAUGACAAACACAGUGAAGCCAACUAUCCCAUAAAAUGAACACUGACAUACUUGUUUUAAUUUUUUUCCCAGCGUAAAAAUAGAAAAAUCAAAAUACUCCUAACAAAACCAGUGAUUUUGAUAGAAAUAUUUCUCCAAUAUACUUGCAUCCACCUACAAAUAUAACCUUUUCAAGAUAAAUCGCUUAUGAUUUCAAUAGUCAAACUGCUGUGUUUGUUGAUGUAAAGAUGUUUUGAAUGGCUAGAUGGUAAAAUAAAUUCUUAAUAAAGUACCCACUGCAAUUUUUAAUUAGCAUAUUCAUUUACAUAUAGAUGUAUACAUCUACCUAUGUGUUUCUCACUGAACGUUUUCCUUGUGACAGAGACAACAAAUACAAUUGUUUCUUUUCCGGAUGAACAAGGAUCUGUUUUGCAAAUGUUUGUAAGAUAUUAUGACAUUUCCAAGAUUUUCUUUGCAUUCUGGAAAGCAGGAGGUAAACAUUUGUAGUCAUUAAGGUAAAGUCUGUUGAUAAACCAUCUUCUGUUUACUGACAGGUAAAUUGUAACUUUCCCUAGCUUUUGAAAUGAGUAACUUCUAUACACCACAAAGUGAGGCACAGCCUGGGAAAGGUGGCUAGACAAGGGGCAAGCCAGGCUUUCUAGCUUCUGGAAGGAUCGAGUGGCCUAGCAGGCAUCUAAGAUAAAGAAAGCAAUGAUUCGGAAGUCCAGUAGGGCCCAUUUGACCGGUAGCAAAAUCGAAAGCACGAAAUAGAUCAAGGUUAGGGAGCCAGACAAAGCCCUUGGAAGAGAGGCAGUAUUGCAGAUCGAAGCAAGCAGUUCAGAGUCUAUGAGGCCUGGGAAUUUAAAAGCAGGAAGAGUAAGAAGCAGAAACAAGAAGCUCCAUCUGAACAGACUCCUCUCUCCAACCUUCAUGAGACCCACAGUGUGUGAUGGGCCACCACAGCACUGGCUUCUAGACUUUUACAGGGAAGCCAGUGAACAAAUUACCUCGUCACCCAGAAAACAAAGAGCUCAGGAACUAUUUUGGAAGUUCCUUCCAGUCUAAGACUAUGGAACUCAGAAUCUAGCAGGUGUGUUCCUUUGGAUAGCAAAACUAAAGAUAUAAAUAUGAAUAAGAAAUUCUUUGCCACUUCUCCUGGGCAAGGUUAUACUUUAUGCCAUCUACUGAGAUAAACCAGAUGAGUCAGUUUGCUUCUGUCAGUUGCUGUGUCACAGAUGACAUCUUCUCAAAAUAAUAUUAUCUCACAGCCAAGAAAUAGCGCUUCGUUUACUGUGUUUUUCUAUCCUGAAACUAAAUGGGCUUACGCUUCAUAGUGGCUAAGAUACUCCACACACAACUAGUACCCAUAGAUCUUUUCUCACUGAUAGGAAAAAAAAAAAAAAAGCAUUAAACACCUUUCAGAGAGUACAUCUGAAACAUUUACGUAUUUUCCUGAUUUAGGCAAAUAUAAUAUUGAAAGUUACCUGUAUGUGGGCAUUUUUUUCUACACUCAUAAAUGCAAAUCAAAUUUUGCCAUUAGCUGUGGCCAACAUUCCUUCCAGGACAAAAGCUUACAUUAGGCCGGGUGCGGUGGCGCACGCCUGUAAUCCCAGCACUUUGGGAGGCCGAGACGGGUGGAUCAUGAGGUCAGGAGAUCGAGACCAUCCUGGCUAACACGGUGAAACCCCAUCUCUACUAAAAAUACAAAAAAAAUUAGCCAGGCAUGGUGGCGGGUGCCUGUAGUCCCAGCUACUGGGGAGGCUGAGGCAGGAGAAUGGCGUGAACCCAGGAGGCGGAGCUUGCAGUGAGCCGAGAUCGUGCCACUGCACUCCAGCCUGGGCGACAGAGCGAGACUCUGUCUCAAAAAAUAAAUAAAUAAAUAAAUUUAAAAUAAAUUUUAAAAAAAUUACAUUAAAGGUGUCACUUAUUUGCAUGAUACCGAGAUUUGGAGUUUAAAGAAAAACCUUAUAAAGACUGUAAUGUCAGAGUUGCUACUAGUUCACAUAAGCAAUAAAAAGUUUUGUAAAUGUGUAAUUCUUAACAUUUAAAAAUAUGUAGGAGUGUGUGUGUGUGUGUGUGUGUGCACACGCACAUUCAUGCUUCUCAACACCCACGACCUAGUGGAAUGGAGUGUUAUUAAAUAAGUUAAUCAGUAUUUUGUUGAAAUCUCAGCAGAUAAUUAGUACUACACGUUGACUCAUUAAUUCAGUUUCCCUUAUCAACCACCCCCAUCAUUUAUUGUUUUGAGUAUGUUUGAUGGAAAACUUAGUCUUCCUCUUUUUUUUUAACACUCGAUUGUUUUUUUCUUUUAAAAUAAAGUCAAUUUUAAUUUUAAAUGUCUUUAAAAGUCCAUCCAUUAUCAAGACUUUGACACAGUGUCUUGAAAUACAGCUUGCCCUAAACUUAAUCUAUGCUUCUGGCUAGGUGUUUCUAUAACAAAUAUCAGGGCACCUGGUUCUUAACCUUCUCAUUUAUACUGUGUUGACAGAAAUAGAUGCAAAUACCUUUUUAAAAAUGCUCCUGGUUUAAUAAGCAUCCUUCAAAUACAGUUAAGUUUAAAUGCCCUGCUCCUGUUCUCAGUCCUUCAGACAUCAAUAUGGCAGGCAGAAUCCAUAAGUCAAUGGAAACUCUUAGCCAUAGAGGGCUGCAGAGAUUAAUUUCAACACCUUGAAAUGCAUCUGGAAGCAAAGAUUUCAUUUUAUGUUGAAGGUGUUAAUUAUAUUUGAUAUUUUUAAAAGUAAAAUCUGUUUUUGAGAAAGCAUCUGCUACCCAGAAAUAUUAUGAGCCACAAAAGAAAUUUUACUGAAGUCUCAAGAUACUUUCUGUGGAUGAUAGAAUCAGUUUUCAAAUGAUAGUCCAUGCUGUCUUUUAAUGCUGACAUACACUGUGGGUCUUAUUCUUCUAUUGACUAUUGACCCAACUGCCUUUCUUUUUCAGUGGAAAAUUUGGGACUAUUUAAUAUUAGAUCUUAUGUUUAACAAUGAAGAGAGUAUAUUAUAAACCACUGACUUGAACAUGUUUCAUUUUAAAAUUUGAGUUGUGAUACAGACAACUAAUGCUCCUAUCCUAUGCCCUCUCUUCAAAGCUAUUCAUUAAAAUAUAACUGGGGAAGUUUGAAAAACAUGCGAGCAAUUCUACAUGCUGCUCAAAGAUACAGACAUGUGUGAUUAAAGUACAGUAUUACAGAAAACCUGGGAAUUAACCAAACUUACAAUAAUGGUUAUGUCAGAGGGGCCAUGGUAGAGAAAAAAAAGGACAUAGAAGUAGGGAAAGGUGCAUUCGUUGCAUGAUGAGAAGUCUGUUUCUUAAGCUGAGUCGUGAUACACAAAGGCUUCUUGCCACUCUUUGUGACAUUUCAUGUGUCUUCAGUGUAUUUAUUGCAUAUAUCUUUUGAUAGGAGAUAUAAAUACUUCAGGAAGCAUGUUACUAGUUUUGCUAUCAGGCUAUCCUUAACAUUUCUUGGUUUUCUCAAUUAUUGAUUGAGUCAGAAAACUGCUUGCCUCAGACAGUGAUACAAACUACUCUACUGCCAAUGUUGCUUGAGAAGACUUUCCUCUGCUUAACAGGAGCCAGGGGCUUCACCUCAACCCUCAUGCUGUGGAGAAAGUCAGACUCAACUGGCCACAGGUUCCUGUUUCUUGGGGCUGCUAAUCACCAUUUCUAACAGAUGCCUGUGGCAUUGCAAACACAAGAUGGAAAACUAUAGCUCUAAACUCCCUUCUGAAGGGUAAGGAAAGGAAGAGGAAGGCAGAUGUUAAAUGAGCCCAGUCUUUCUCAUCUCAAAAAAUUCAGAGCUGCCUGUUAGAGCACAAGAGCUCUCAGAGCUCCCAACCACACUGCCCACUCCCCAUAGUGUUGCCUCUCCCCUUUCCUCUUUAAGACGCAGGAGCGAAUCGUGGUCUUUGUGCUUUCACUGCAAUCUAUCCCAGGGGAAGAGUUCUCCCGGGUAUCUGUGGGAUGCCCUUGCUGCAUGUGAGGCACAAAUGGCUUCAGGGACCAGGAUCCUCACUCACUCUGCAGUCCAUUUUUCUAAAUUGGAAUUUGCGAUCGGUUUCUUCAGGUGUCCCACCAUCAUCUAUCAUUAUCUGAGUUAUUCCUUAUCCUCUCCCAACCCCAAGGAGAGGAUCUUAAUUGUUUUUAUAAACUGACAGAAGGAAUUGGUGAUUCUUGGAAGAUAAUUUUAAAUGGUUAUAUUACUUUCCUAUUACUGCAUUUACUGCAUUUAAAUAGCAGGUCUAAGGUGGGGUGCGAGAAGAUGUGACCCCUAGGAAUAUUGGUAUGACCUUUCUCAAGCAAUUUGAAGUCCUUUAGAUCUGAAAAUUUAAUGUCUUCAAUAUCAUUUCACAGAUGAGAAAAUUAAGGCACAUAUAGUGACAUAUUUAGGAGCUGAAGUGUGUUACAGAAACAAAGUUUUUUUGUAUAAGCCUUUCCCUACAUGGGAUGUUAUCAUUGUCACCUAUGUGCCUUUCAGGAAGCACCAAGUGCAGUAUGCGUGACUCAGUUGGACCCCUAGUUCCCUUCUAUUUCUCCAGCUGGCAGGAGACAGCAAAGGACAGUGGAGGUGGUUAUUUUGUGGCCCACAUUUCUGCCAUUAAAAGGGACAUAAGAGACUAUGUAGUGUGGCCAAUUUUUUUUUUUUUUUUUUUGAGAGAGAGAGUCUGGCUCUGUCGCCCAGGCUGGAGUGCAGUGGCACCAUCUCGGCUCACUGCAAGCUCCACCUCCCGGGUUCACGCCAUUCUCCUGCCUCAGCCUCCCGAGUAGCUGGGACUACAGGUGCCCACCACCACGCCCGGCUAAUUUUUUUGUAUUUUUAGUAGAGACGGGGUUUCACCAUGUUAGCCAGGGUGGUCUCAAUCUCCUGACCUCGUGAUCCACCUGUCUCGGCCUCCCAAAGUGCUGGGAUUACAGGUGUAAGCCACCAUGCCCGGAAUAUGGCCAUUAUUUUAAGUGUUUUUAUUAUUGCUCUGGUUCUCCCUUUAGGGAGGCAUUCAGUGAGUAUACCCCAUCUGUCACAGGCCCCCACCACUCCCUGUGGUCUUACACUCUGCUGAAUUCAUACAUUUAGGUAACUUCCCUGGCCCUCCUGAGAAUCACUUAUUUUUGUAACCUCCUGUAUUUGAGAUGUAGGAAACUGGGGCCUGAGGAGAAGUUGACUUGCCUUGGGUCCCACAGUGGUACAGGCAGAUCUAGAACUCAGAUUUUCCAGGGCUCUUUCAGUAGGCUGUGGUUGAGCAGUAGUCAAGACCACCUCUUCAAGAAGGGAAAAACAUUUGUCUUCUCUUUCUCCUCUUUCUUCCUUCUGCCUCUCACUGUAAGAAGAAACGUGUUAAUAAGUUGCUAAUACCUUACUCUAGGUGUAUUUCAUGUUACACCAGCCAGUGCUUGUAUUCUCAAUGACCAUAAGGAGAGGAAUGCGGAAGAAUUGAUUUCUGUACUAAAAGUUCAGACUCUGUGGCACUUGUGAUAUUUCUGGACAACUGACUCUUCUCUAUUGCCUUUCGAAUCAUACAGUGGCAAAGCUGCUCACCCAUGUGUGUAUAAAGCUGACCCUUCAUCAGAAAGGCAGCCCCCAGUGUCUCCCCACACAGGGCAGAAGAGCAGAGGGAGCAGGUGGCAAUGUGGCAGCACCUUGAACUGUGCAUCACUGGGCCUGCUCCCCCUCAUCCCAAAGCAAUAACCCAGAAAUUACAUCCUGAGACUUACUUCCUCAGAAAGAAAAGGAAGGGGAGGGAUAACUUAAAAAGGAGAAACUUCUAAUAUGGUAUUAGACUGUAAUUCAUAGGGAAAUUUAUGCCUGAGAUAUGAAUUUCUGAAAAUAAGGGGCUUUUUUGGAAGGGAAACACUGACACAUCCUUAAUUAUAGAGUAAUAAAUACCAAUGGUAUAUUAUCUUUCGAUAUUUCCUUACACAGAUAUCAAAGCAUGCAGCUGUUUUUGAAAACUGAUAAUCAAGUACAAUAUAAGUAUAUUACAUCUUGCACUUACAACACACCCUUCAACUAAGCAGCAUCAUGGAGCACUUAACGGUGAGAAACAGAGCUGCUCAUAGUAGAAACCUAACUGAACAAAUUAGCUUUGAAUUGUAACUUAAGAAUCGUAGUCAAACCAAAGCGUCUGUCCUUGCCAGGAAAGGCAUUCCAAAGGCAGAGAGCAUGCCAAGUAAAAAGGCUUUGCUUCAGGAUUAUGGAGACAGUUCUGAAAAGCCAGCAUAACUUAAUGAUCAAUCAGAAAAAUAUAGAGCAGUAACUACACAACUGAAGGAUGCAUAAAAAUUGUACAAAACGUUAAUAGUGGAAUGGGGAGGUAGGAUGGGAUUUUACGGGCAAGUAUUAAGCUCUUGGAAAGCUUCAUUUGUUGCCCUCAAUCCACACAGCAGAAAGAAAGAGAAAGAGACAAACAUGGUCAAAGAAAAGUAUGUGGACAAAUGUGGGGGGUAGAAAAGGAAAUGAAGGUUAAGCAAGGCCAAUAUAAUUCAGAAUAAAAGGGAGGGAGGGAAGUAUAAGGAGCCAGCUGUAAUUACUGAAUGUUACAUUAAGAAGAGCUGAAAUUGAGAGGGGGAGGUCUUGAGUAUUUUACUAAGUGGAUUAAUGUCCUCUUCCUCGGGUGUCUGAAGUUGCAGAUUUUAAUUUAUUUGGUGCAGGGAUUUAUUACAGAAUUCUUAAUGGGUGGGGAGAUAAACAGGGACAAUUAUAAGCUCUUAAGAAGAAGAAAAGAGGACCAUAUAAUACUUUCUAUAAAUUUAACUGUAAUAAACAGGGUUUCAAGCUAUGGACAAAGAUAGUCAAAAAAAGCAUUUAUUCCAUGAUAUAGGACUAAAAGGGAAAUAAGAGGUGUGUCCAAAAAACUUAAAGACCAAAACAAAGAAAGAAAAACCCACAUAGAUGUGUGAUGCCAGGAUUUUGAAUGACUUGGGAGCUAGUUAUUGCCGCUCUCCUUUCUCCACCCAUUUAAAAAAAUAAAUCAUAACUCUGGCAUUUAAAAACCUACUCAUGAACAUCAUUUAUUAAUAUAAACUUAAUCCUGUGCUAUUCUUUGGUGGGUGGUAAGAACAUGAAUUAACAACAACUGGACUAAAACGAUGGCAACAGGAUGAUCCACUCAAACACAGGAAAGCUGUAAGAAAAAGAAAAACUCCUAAUCUGCUCUUUCACCUUACUUAUUUUACAGAAGGAGAAAGCCAAAAAGGGGAGAGCAUGUGGCUAAACCACAGAAAGACUAGAUGCCUAAAGGAAAAAUUUUAAAGUGUUCCUAAAUAGGUAUUAGAAGGGGAAGGGGGAUGUAAAGCUUAUGUGAUUUACAUCAUUUUGUUAAUCUGCUAAUCUACUUCCCUGGAAGGUGAGAAAGAGUGUUGUCUGCCUUCUGCAAUUGAAGAGACUAGGGCAGAAACUUAAUUAUGUUCUUACCCUGUGUAUACCUGGCUGUCAUCUGGCUGGCAACUAGUCCACAAACUAUUGGUUCAGGCAUUUGCCUGGCAAUAAUGUUAGCCAUCAUUUAAAUUGUUAAAUAUGGAUCAGAAGAUCUCUAAGAAUUACUGAUAUGCAGCUAUUAAUACUGGAUGUAAAUAAUAUUAUUUGGGGUGUGGGUAAAUCAUUUGACUGGAACCACAUUUAAAAAAAGGACUUGGAAAUUUUAUUUUUGAAAUGCUGUUGGGGAGAUGGCAUUGAUGAAAAAAAAAAUUGAAAAUGGAAAAAAACAUCAUCUACAAAGAGAUGGGUAAAAAUGACUAAGCAAAGAAGCCUUGUCACCUUCGACCUGAUGCUUCAUUGUAUCAGAAGAAAGUAAACAGAUUGCUAACAAAGAGACCACCCCUUCUAAUUUCCAAAACCGGCCCAGCAACAAGAGGGAGAAAAUAGAGAAGAGUGCACUGCGUGGUGGCUCAGGGUGAUCCUUUAAUUUGAGUGUUAAAAAUGAGGGCACAGACCUAGAGGUUUUUAAUGGUCCGCGGGUGGACUUCAGAUUCUGAACACUCCUCCACCUUCUGUGGAGAAUUCGGGACACGGUGGAGUUUAACCAGUAUCUUAAAUCCCAGGGACAGGGUGGAGAUUGCUUUGUGAUCCUGAUUAAUUAAAAGGAAAGAAAUCAAAGCAGACAUCUCUCCUUUUUCCAUUUGAGCCGCAGAGCCAUGGAGGGGAACUUGUGCUCUCUGGUGCUUGCAGCUAUGUUCCCUGGCUUUCAUCGUCUUGGCUUUUCCCCUUGUAUUUCUAAUGCUGUGAUACCAGGCCAAUAAAAUGGAAUCUACAAAACUGCAAAACAAAA